GUGACGGCUGCGUGCGGCGGGAAUCAUGGCUGCUCGCAGAGCUCUGCACUUCGUAUUCAAAGUGGGAAACCGCUUCCAGACGGCGCGUUUCUAUCGGGACGUCCUGGGGAUGAAGGUGCAGGCCGGGGCCGACAGGGGCUGGCGCGCGAGGCUGGAACCGGCGCCCGAGCCGGCCCUGGCGGAGGGAGGGGAAAAUGGGUGUGUCGUGAACCUAAGCCGGAGGGUGUCCGACCUUAGGCCCUGCGCGGUGUUCAGCUUCAGGAGCGUGGCGAGUUGCCGUUGGGGAUCAUAGGCCUUGGAGAAGGGCCUAACACGAUUAGUCCCCGCGGUGUGCCCACGCACGUCCUUUCAUUUAAGCCACUCGUAAACGUUUAUUGAGCCCCGCCCUUGUGGAGCUUACCGUCUACCGGAAAAGACGGUUCUGCGGCAUGAGGAAUUUGAAGAAGGCUGCAAAGCUGCCUGUAAUGGGUAUGAUACCUUGUUUCUUAAAAUCUCCUUUAGGCUCUGACUACACCCGGAUAACAGAAGACAGUUUCUCAAAGCCUUAUGAUGGGAAAUGGAGUAAAACAAUGGUGGGAUUUGGGCCUGAGGAUGAUCAUUUUGUCGCAGAACUGACUUACAAUUAUGGCGUCGGAGACUACAAGCUUGGCAAUGACUUUAUGGGAAUCACGCUCGCUUCUAGCCAGGCUGUCAGCAACGCCAGGAAGCUGGAGUGGCCACUGACGGAAGUUGCAGAAGGUGUUUUUGAAACCGAGGCCCCGGGAGGAUAUAAGUUCUAUUUGCAGAAUCGCAGUCUGCCUCAGUCAGAUCCUGUAUUAAAAGUAACUCUAGCAGUGUCUGAUCUUCAAAAGUCCUUGAACUACUGGUGUAAUCUACUGGGAAUGAAAAUUUAUGAAAAAGAUGAAGAAAAGCAAAGGGCUUUGCUGGGCUAUGCUGAUAACCAGUGUAAGCUGGAGCUACAGGGCGUCAAGGGUGGGGUGGACCAUGCAGCAGCUUUUGGAAGAAUUGCCUUCUCUUGCCCCCAGAAAGAGUUGCCAGACUUAGAAGACUUGAUGAAAAGGGAGAACCAGAAGAUUCUGACUCCCCUGGUGAGCCUGGACACCCCAGGGAAAGCAACAGUACAGGUGGUCAUUCUGGCCGACCCUGACGGACAUGAAAUUUGCUUUGUCGGGGAUGAAGCAUUUCGAGAACUUUCUAAGAUGGAUCCAGAGGGAAGCAAAUUGUUGGAUGAUGCAAUGGCAGCAGAUAAAAGUGACGAGUGGUUUGCCAAACACAAUAAACCCAAAGCUUCAGGUUAACGGAAGACAUGAUGCAGAGCAAGCCUCUGUGAUUCCUGCCCAGCACCUGUGAGGCCUGACGUGUCAGUUCCCAAUAAAUGCUCUUCUGAUUUGUUUCCCGUACAGGCAAGGAGGCUUGGGUAGUGCAGAUUUGUGUAUUUCAAUCUUUGAAAGCUCUGAUGUAAUUUAGAAAUGAAAUCCAAUCAUGAGUCCAGGUAGAGAACGCCUGCUGUAAUCUACACUGUUGCUGGGACUGCGCAUUCUGUAUAUAACUGUGUUGGAUGAGUGACAGAUGAUUGUCCAGACUAGGACAGCGGCAUGAACAUGACUUUGGUUGGGAUUGCGGAUAGUUAGGGUUACCUCUGAAUCGUGUAGCUUUUAUGAGAGCAGCUGUGCAAGUGAAUCCACAUUAAUGCCUUGUCGUGGUGCCAUUCCCAGCGCCUGACGAUACGCUCUUCUAUUGUCUUAUUCUGGCAGGUUUUGACGUUUUAAAUUUUUUAAAGAAAUUUUAUUCCUUGGACCAAAAGGUUUGGUUAACCACCCCCCUCUUACUUGCUUUCACAUUUUGAGUGUCCAGAGGAAACAGAAAGGAAUGAGUGUGUGACGUUGCUGCACGCCUGACUCUGUGCGAGCUUCUUUCUGUGUAUAUAUUUUGUUUUAUUUUUUUCCGUGUAUAUUUUUAAUCCCGACAGAACAUCAUGUGAGAUUUCUUUAAAAUGGAUUAAACGAUUUCUUCAGCCUGAAAAAAAAGGUUUUGAAAAUGUUUUCUUGUAGUUUUGUUUGGUUCUAAACAACAAAUAGGUUUUAAUCACUCGAAAUGGAAUUAUAUUGUGUAUUCAUUGAAUAAAUUUUUUUUGAAAGUAA